CAAACAGCCUGCGAGCAGAGCCUCCUGAGGUGUAUUUCGGGUCUUGCUGGGGCUGAGAGAGACCACAGCCCUUUGGGGGGUACAAACAAGAGUUCAGUUGCUGUGAAUUCUGCCACUGUGCCCAGCUCUGAAGCCUCAGCUCUUGCCAAACAGACCCGAGACCCAUGUCAGCCCCACUGGAUGCCGCCCUCCACGCCCUUCAGGAGGAGCAGGCCAGACUCAAGAUGAGGCUGUGGGACCUGCAGCAGCUGAGAAAGGAGCUCGGGGACUCCCCCAAAGACAAGGUCCCAUUUUCAGUGCCCAAGAUCCCCCUGGUAUUCCGAGGACACACCCAGCAGGACCCGGAAGUGCCUAAGUCUUUAGUUUCCAAUUUGCGGAUCCACUGCCCUCUGCUUGCGGGCUCUGCUCUGAUCACCUUUGAUGACCCCAAAGUGGCUGAGCAGGUGCUGCAACAAAAGGAGCACACGAUCAACAUGGAGGAGUGCCGGCUGCGGGUGCAGGUCCAGCCCUUGGAGCUGCCCAUGGUCACCACCAUCCAGGUGAUGAUGUCCAGCCAGUUGAGUGGCCGGAGGGUGUUGGUCACUGGAUUUCCUGCCAGCCUCAGGCUGAGUGAGGAGGAGCUGCUGGACAAGCUAGAGAUCUUCUUUGGCAAGACUAGGAACGGAGGUGGCGAUGUGGACGUUCGGGAGCUACUGCCAGGGAGUGUCAUGCUGGGGUUUGCUAGGGAUGGAGUGGCUCAGCGUCUGUGCCAAAUCGGCCAGUUCACAGUGCCACUGGGUGGGCAGCAAGUCCCUCUGAGAGUCUCUCCGUAUGUGAACGGGGAGAUCCAGAAGGCUGAGAUCAGGUCGCAGCCAGUUCCCCGCUCGGUACUGGUGCUCAACAUUCCUGAUAUCUUGGAUGGCCCGGAGCUGCAUGACGUCCUGGAGAUCCACUUCCAGAAGCCCACCCGCGGGGGCGGGGAGGUAGAGGCCCUGACAGUCGUACCCCAAGGACAGCAGGGCCUAGCAGUCUUCACCUCUGAGUCAGGCUAGGGGCCUCCCCUUCUCAUCCUCCCCACCCCCCCGCCAAGGUUCUCACACUGGCCUGGGCUUGGGUGCCCAUAUAGGAGGUCUGUAUGUUCACCAACAGUGCGGAGGGGUCACACAUUGCAAAACACUGCCCAGAACAGUAAAAAGAGCCUGCAUGCCA